CCCUACUAGCUCCGCCCACAGCUGUGUCCGGAAGCAGCAAGCGUGCCUGGGCAGAGACCCCCAGAGUGUAAAGAGGUCCUGGGACAGGCUUUGCACGUUCCACAAGAGGAUUAAAGGAAAUAAUGUGUGUCCCAUGCUCAGCCCUGCACCUGCCACAGUAAGCACCUGGUGAGUGGGAGUAUCUGAUCUUGUUAUUGAGGAUGCAGAGGCCGACUCCCCUGUUCUCUGCUUCCUUCGCCCUCCCCUUGCCAACCUGCUUCAACACAGGAUCCUGCAGGACCUCCUCCUUUGCCAUAUGCUCCUUCAGCAGUUCUGUCUGCACAAUCCCCGGCCACAGAGACACACAGCUGACCCCAUGGCGCCGCAGCUCGUGGGCACAGUCAGCAGCCAGCUUGUCACACUGUGGAGAGGCGGAAGGCAGGGAGCCCCAAGGUCUCAGCUGCCCACGCUCCCCAGUGUGAUGCCUACUCUAGCCAACCAAGAGGAGCACAAGCAAAGGAACUGUCCAUGGAUGAGGCAGAGGAGGAGCUGAGAGGAGCCAGCCUUACCAUUCUGACCACUGGGGAUUGUACCUCCUGAGCUAUAGUGUCUCGCUGUGUCGUCUAGACUGGAGUGCAGUGGUGUGAUCAUGGCUCAACUCCUAGGCUCAAGCGAUCCUCCUGCCUCAGCCUCCGGAGUAGCUGCUGGGACUGCAGGAACGUGCCACCAUGCCUGGCUCAAACACAAAGUUUUUUCAUAAAACUCACUUGGCGGCAAAAUUCUACCUUACCUGAAGUUAUUUACGGGGUUUUUAAUUUCCACUUUGAAUAAAUAUUCACAUCUUGUUGAGUAGUAUUAUAGUUUCAGGUAAGGGAUUAGGAAAGGAGCUGUUAAGUGGAAGGGCUCUCUCGGGUGGUUUCUGCAACUGUGGUCCCAGAGGAAGCACUCACCUCCUGAGCAACAACGCGAAGGGUGUCCAGAUGGCGGCCAGUGAUGUAAACUGUGGCGCCUGCUUUGCAGAGCUGCAAGGCAAUGCCACGGCCAAUACCCCUGGAGGCACCAGUCACCACACACACUUGGCCAUUCAUGGGAGCUGCCAUGACUCACAGGCAAAGGAGGCAGGUCUGUGGAAGCAAAGACUUACUCUGAGGGAAGCCUGGAGACUGUGUGUGUGUUGGGGCGAGGUUGGGGGGUAGGGGAGAACCUCACUAGGGCUAAGAGGAGGAGCCAAGGUAAGAAUCCUUUGAGGGGAGAGGAGUCAGAGGCUGACAACUGGGUGCGGGCCUGAGGACAAGGCUGACUGUCUUUUGGGAGGCCCAGAGAGUGAAGAAGGGGCUGAGUGGGACUGUCCAGAGGUGGACAACUACUACAACCCUCUGAGUGUGGCUGCCUGGAUAUGGGAAUCUGGCGCGGCAGCCCCUCGGGGCGCGUCCACGCAGAGUCCUGGGCUAUCUGAAGCUCCGGUCCCUGGCCUGACCCAGUCCGGCUGAGCCAGAGGCGCAGCUUCCGGGCCGGGGAUGAGCGCGAAGCCUGGAGAUCCUAAGCCCUAAGUGGGACGAGCGUGCGCCGCUUACCUGCCACCUGCGCUGCCGCUGAGGUCUGCAGAUUGCGGGGCUGCGGUGGAAGUCUGGGUUCUCGCCCAGAUUGAGCCGGCGACGUGGAGGCAGUGUUCAAGGAUUGAUUCUGUAGUAGGACCCGGGGCGAUUCUGUGCUGAGGUAGAGGGGCAGAGUCCCAGGCCAAAGUUAGAACCUGCGGAUGGGGGCGGAGCGAUCUGGGUGACACACCCACCCCGCCCGGCUGGGGCGGCGCGGAACUAUGACGUAGUAGCUGCGUCAGGAGCGCGCCCGCGUUUCUAAACUUUGUCUGGAUAAGGCGCACGCUUGGCGACGUCGAAGGUCCGUCCGCAGUUAAGGAAGCUUUUGCAGCCGGACAGGUCGCGAAGCACACAUGGGGCAGGGUCCGCGCUCUCCACACAAGGUGGGGCGCCGGUUCCCAGCUGGUGGCAAACGGGGGCGCGGGGCCAAGGGGUCGGGGCGCCCCUUACCAGGCCGUAAGCGGCAACCCUGGCCGCCUCCGGAUGGGCGCUCGGAGCCGGCUCCAGAUUCGCACCCGCACCUGAGCCCGGAAGCUCUGGGAUAUUUCCGCCGGGCGCUGUCAGCAUUGAAAGAGGCUCCCGAGACUGGGGAAGAACGAGAUCUGAUGGUGCACAAUAUAAUGAAGGAAGUAGAGACUCAGGCCCUAGCUUUGUCCACGAACAGGACUGGCAGUGAGAUGCUGCAGGAACUGUUGGGAUUCAGUCCCUUGAAACCGCUUUGUCGCGUGUGGGCUGCUCUGCGCUCUAACUUGCGCACUGUGGCCUGUCACCGAUGCGGGGUCCAUGUAUUACAAAGUGCUUUGCUACAGCUCCCUCGAUUGCUGGGGAGUGCUGCAGAGGAGGAGGAGGAGGAGGAGGAGGAUGGAAAGGAUGGUCCCACGGAGACCCUGGAGGAGCUGGUCCUGGGACUAGCCGCUGAGGUGUGUGAUGAUUUUCUUGUCUACUGUGGAGACACACAUGGCAGCUUCGUGGUCAGAACUCUGCUUCAGGUGUUAGGAGGGACUAUUCUGGAGUCUGAGAGAGCCAGGCCCCGUGGUUCCCAAUCAUCUGUUUGUGAUCUCCCCACUGCACAUGUUCUUAAUCUUCCUUCAGAAGCACAGAAGACCCCAGCUCAGGAAUGUAAGCCAGCUGAUUUUGAAGUCCCUGAAACCUUUUUGAAUCGCCUUCAGGACCUGAGCUCCUCCUUUCUGAAGGACAUUGCAGUGUUUAUCACUGAUAAGAUCUCCAGCUUCUGUCUUCAAGUGGCUUUACAGGUUUUACACCGCAAACUUCCCCAGUUUUGCGCUCAUCUCUGCAAUGCUGUGAUUGGCUACCUGAGUACUCGCGGUUCCUCAGUAGAUGGCAGUCCCCUACUGCUAUUUCUCCGAGAUCAGACGAGUUCCAGACUCCUGGAGCAGGUCCUGCUGGUGUUGGAGCCCCCAAGACUCCAGAGCCUCUUUGAGGAGCACUUGCAGGGGCAGCUGCAGACCCUGGCUGCACAUCCCAUUGCCAACUUCCCUUUGCAGCGCUUACUGGAUGCAGUCACUACCCCUGAGCUGCUGUCCCCUGUGUUUGAGGAGCUGAGCCCUGUCUUGGAAGCUGUAUUGGCCCAGGGCCACCCAGGGGUAGUCAUUGCCCUGGUGGGGGCCUGUCGCAGAGUUGGGGCCUACCAAGCCAAGGUCCUACAGCUCUUGUUGGAGGCAUUCCACUGUGCAGAGCCCUCAUCCCGGCAAGUGGCCUGUGUGCCUCUCUUUGCCACUUUGAUGGCUUAUGAGGUGUACUAUGGACUGACGGAGGAGGAGGGGGCAGUGCCUGCAGAGCACCAGGUGGCAAUGGCCGCAGCCAGAGCCUUGGGGGAUGUGACAGUCCUUGGGUCUCUACUGCUCCAGCAUCUGCUGCACUUCUCCACUCCUGGUCUUGUACUUCGAAGUCUGGGUGCCUUGACGGGACCACAGCUUCUGUCCCUUGCCCAAAGUCCCGCUGGCUCUCAUGUGCUCGAUGCCAUCCUGACCAGCCCCUCUGUGACGCGCAAGCUGCGCCGCCGUGUGCUGCAGAACCUAAAGGGACAAUAUGUGGCUCUGGCCUGUAGUCGCCAUGGCAGCCGUGUGCUAGAUGCCAUCUGGAGUGGAGCAGCCUUGAGGGCCCGGAAGGAAAUUGCUGCUGAGCUUGGGGAGCAGAACCAGGAGCUGAUAAGAGACCCUUUCGGCCACCAUGUGGCUCGAAAUGUGGCCUUGACUACCUUCCUAAAGCGGCGAGAGGCUUGGGAACAGCAGCAGGGUGCGGUGGCCAAGCGGAGGCGGGCAUUGAACUCCAUACUUGAAGACUGAGGCUUUGGAUCUGGGACUGGGUGUUGAUGGGGGAGGGCAAAAUGGGGUAUCCACCCCAUCCCUUUCCUGGUUUAAAUUGGAGUCAGAAGUCUUAGUGGUAAAUAUUUGAUAUUUUUAUUGGAAAUGUUUUUGUUAGUUUGAGGGGAAGGGUAUGAAGACAGAUCUCAAGGUAAAGUCAGAGAGGGCUGUCAUCAGUAUGCUGGGGAGUUUAGGGACAGGAGGCAUUGGUAGGGGAUUAGAUGUAGCAGCAGUCAGGCUGGGAUCAAGAUGCCUGGGGGACAUCUUGAUCUUGGCCUUUCAGGGCAAGUGGGAGGCCAGAAAGGUGGCUAGGAAAGAACAGCAUUCUUCAGGUAAGGGUAUAGACUUGGGAUGUGAGGCGUUAUGCUGAAAGGUUCUGUCACGAGGGGAUCAGAGGACAGUGGGGAAAUUGGGUGGGUUAUCUAGCCUGUACUGUCUGCAGGUCCUGAAAUUUGAUGCUGUCAUAGUCUUUGCAGUGGGUCGGUUGGAAUGAUUCUGGGGGCAGAAGCUCAGAGCCCCUUAGUAGGAAUGGAGGCGGCCCUUCUGCUGCCACUGCUCAGCCCCCUCCACUGCAUGACGAAGGGUGGAGGAAAUUCCCAGCAACAUAUGGCCCAGGCCUUGCAGCAGUGUGGAGGUCCAACGAAGGAGCUCCCUGAAUGGCAGAGACAAGAGGAAAUCAGAUGAUUUGGAAAACUUGGGAGGAAGCCAUCAAGCUGGGAGAUGAGGACUUUCCACAAGCAAGAGCUAACUAGGGGUAGGUGGGUGCAAGAGGACGAAUUAUGGGGACUAUCCAACUGUAGGGGAUGGGGCAGUAUGACAUGUUGAUUUCUGACCUGAGUACUUUCUUUGGGCCAAGUCCUUGAAAGUCACAACUCAUAGAGUAGAGCCCGUAGAAUGUGGCUUUGACAUUCAGGCUGCCAAAGAGGUCUCGAGGGUUUUGCUUGUACACGUCAAAGGUGAAUCGGGCGAUGUCCUUGCUGUGCUUGGGCCUCUCCCGUCCCAGGCCAUAUGACAGCACUCCACUCUGUAGGACACCCUUGUCAGUGCAGUAGAUCCUCAUACCAGACACCCACCACUAAUCUCCAUCAGCACUGGGUCAGACCCUCCCUCGCUUGGACUUUCUGUCCACUGUGUGACAUCCUUGACAAUUCCACAACUCCUCCUGCACCUGGUCCCCAGGAUCAGGGUUAAGCUAGAGAGGAAGCCCGGGAAAGCUCUAAAGGACAGGCAUUGGAAGCAGCCCCAGUAUAGGCCUCUUACCCUUGUAGGGCUCCAGCUCUGACCAGACUGCAACACCAUCAGGCACGUGUCAUCCUCCAGCAGCUGGAAGAAGUCCUCACUGUCCACUGCAGUUCCAUCCUCCUCUAGCACCAGGGUUAGCACUCCAUUCAGCAGUAGGGUCUCCAAUGCCUGCCCAAUGGCAAGAAGCAAGAAGGGCAGGUCUUAUCCCAUGCCCCUUCCCUCUUUAGCUGCCCAACAUCCAUCAGUUGGCUCUAGACAUUGGUCGAUGUCCCACUUUGACUUUCCGGCACUUUGAUACCUCCUAAAGGUUGCAGCUCUCCGUGUUCUUCAGUUUUUGGGGGAUCCUAGCUAGAGGCUGACCUUUUUCCUCUUUGCUCCUACCAUGUCAUUGGCAUCUCCCCUUGCUCCCCUCCAAGUCACUUCUGGUUUGGAAUUGGAAAGCAAGCCAGGUUCUCACGAAGUCCACCCUUCUGUCUUAUCUACAAUGCUGCACCUCACUUCCCACACCCUCAAGAGUUCUCCAGAAGUGUUUUCAGUAAUAGUGUUUAACCUUUUUGAGUCCUUACUCUGUGCCAGGUAUGAGGACUUUACCUACAUUAUCCUCUUACUCCUUUCAACAACCCUAGGAGGUGAUGUAUUAUUAUUGCCUUUUUAUAGUUGAAGAAACUGAGGUUUUGGUAGGUUGAACAACUUCCCAAGGUUUGACAGGCAGGAAGUGGCAGAAUCAGAAUUUGAACUUGAUUUGUCACACAAAUCACCUUUCCAUACUAGCUUCUGAAUUCUGUCCCUCGAACUCUCCCUAUCUCCUGCUAACCCCUGCUCCCAUAGAAAAGCUCACUCGGUGGAAAAUGAACAAAUUGACCAGAGCUCAUUAGGCCCACUCCGCUGCUUUUAGCCCUCAGAGGGAGGGGCAGCUGUGUGACUUCAGCCCUCUGCUCCAUCAUCACAAGUUGCCACUGUUGUGGAGCCCCUUGGCUACCCCUGCUAUAGGAACCGAGGAACUUGGCCUACUUACUUUGGCUAGCAGCUCCUGGCGGGUGGCAGCUGUCAGGCCUUUCCGGAUGGUCCGCUUGUGAUCACAGACACGGAAAGGUCGCUGGGGUGGUGGAGCUGAGGUCCAGACCCUCCGUCCAAACUCCGAGCUUAUAUUAGAUACUGACCUGGUAGUUGAGAAGAAAAGUCAAGAAGGGGCGAGGAGGGGCUUGGUGAGUGUAAAGGGCAUGAUGAGGGUAGAGUGGCUAGAGGGCUAGGGAGGGAGAGAUCUAGGUUUAUCGAUUAGGGAUGAGGGAGAGACCAUGGAGUGCAGGUGGGGGCGGGUGGCUCAGGAGCUUGACAAGCCCACUGUGGAGUGGGGAGCAGGAGAGGAAGGGGUACUGGUUAGUCUCCUAGGGGCUGAGUGGAGUAUUGUUGCCCUGCCUAUAUCCCCUAAAGGUGGAGGGUAGAGCGGAGGGUUAGCAGUCACCUGAGUAAGUCACUGGGGUUCAGAGCUGAGAGGUACUCCAUGGUGGACCGGAGAGUUCCUUCCCUGGAACUUCUGGGCUGGGUGGUUCUCUCCUGUGCUGGGGCUUUAGUGGUGUUUUCUGUUACAAACCUGGGAUCUCAGCCCAGGACAAGGUGGGAAUGAGUCAAGCCUGGACUCUGGCCCCCCUGCCUGGCCAGUAAGAAGGGCAAAGUCCAAGGGGAGGGAUGAGGGAGGGGCCAGAUGGGGUCCUGGAGGAAGAAUUGCCUGGCAAAAGCCAUUGGAGCUUGUAUGUGUGUCUUUGGUGAUGACAUGUGUUGUGAGGGUAGAUGGGAACCAUGUAAAAGGAUGAAAUGUGACUUCUGGUGUUUUUUUAUUUCUAUGGAGGGAAUUUCUGGGGACGGUUUCUGGCUCUCAGGCUCUGAGAAGCUGCAGUUUAUGAGUGGCUCUGUGUGUGCUGCCACCUACUGGAGAAGCCAUAAGCUGCAGCUUUAGGAAAAGGGAACCCGGGGCAGAGUGUGGGGAAGUGGGAUGGCAGCAUGGCAGGGCUUUGGAAAAUGAGAGGUGAGACUGUGUCCAGGAAGGGUGUAAGGAGAGGAUGGAUCCUGAUACAUGGAUUCAGGAUCAUUAGGGUCCUGUCUGGGACACUGGCCUUCCUGCUUACCUGCUCUUUCCUUCCUCCUUGGUCGGAGGAGGGGCUGGCUCACUGCUCUGGCUUCAUUUUCCAGAGCUGCCUGCUGCAGUCACACUUAGGUCAUCUUCUCUCACUUUUCUCCUUUUGCCGAUUAGUGGACGUGACAGAGAUGUGAAUGGGGCAGGGAUGUCCUUUGAUGGCAUCAAGACUUUAGCUUCUGGUGCGCUGUGUCCCAGCUCUGAUUUCAGUUGCAGCCGUGAUGGACAGUUGCAUGGAAGCUGAGACUCUCACUGACAGUGAAACCCUCAAAUGAACACAAUCCCUGCUUUCCUGCCAAGGAUCCUUGUAGGGUCCCCCAGCUUCCCCACUUUUUUUCUGUGUCCUGACAAAGAAACACAGAGUAACUUGAUUGCCCUGUGACCUGGCCAGUUGCAUUUCCCCUGCAGGCUUGAGCCCAAGCCAGAGCCUUGAAAAGGUAUUCAGGUUGUUGCCCAAAACACUGAAAAAAACUGGCCCUGGCCCUGAACCAAAUACCUUGAACCCUCGUAAACUCCAUACCCUGACCCCCUUGUUUUGGAUAUACCCAGGUAGAACAACUCUCUCUCACUGUCUGUUGUGAGGAUACGCUGUAGCCCACUCAUUAAGUACAUUCUCCUAAUAAAUGCUUUGGACUGAU